UAGCUUACAAGGCUUUCACUCAACUAUUUUAUAAUUUUGAUAAUGACUUAAUUGAUUAGUUGAUAUAUUGUUAAAAUAAAUAUAUUAAUGAAUUUAUGAUAAAUAAGGCAGAUAAAUAAGACAUGCAAUUAGGAAGACAUGUUAAACAAAUUGUUAUAAUAAUACAAUCACUCUCAGCUUAGGAUAGCUCCUGGCCACUUUCUCUCUGGGUGGUUUUUACUCUGGGAGUAGUUUAAAUCAUUAUCUAGUAGUAGUUUAAAGCAUUAUCUUUGCCUAAGAGCUUUCGCUGACUCCCCACAUUUGCAUUGUACUAAGAGUUUUCUCUGACUCCCCACAUAGGUCUAGACCCUAGUAUUAUAAGAUUCUCAUUGUACUUGCACUUUGCCUUCAAAGUACUAAUCACGGUUUUGUUAGUGAUUUGUGUGAUGAUUUGUUGAAUCUUUUUUUUUUUCCCACUAGGGUGUAAGCCCCAUGUUCCAUCUUGAUCACCAUGUUUCUAGCCCAGUGCUGGCAUAUAGUGGGUUCUCACUAAUAUAUCUGUAGAGUAAAUGAAGAAAUGCAUGAGUGACAUGACAGGAGAAUUUAAGGAUGCCAUGGGAGCAUAAAACAGAGGGAGCCACCUGGGUGAGGAGAGCUGAGAAAGACUUCUGGAGAGGCGACAUUUGAGCUGAGAAAGGAAAGACAAGUGGGAGAGUCCUCCAGGUGUAGAAGUUGGAGAGAUGAGCGCUCCAGUUAGGUAGUAUUUGAAGCUGAUGUAGAAAAGGAGUCUUGAGCCAGCUUGUGAAGGACUAUUGGAGAGUUUUAUUUUUAUUUUUAUCUUUUUUUUAAUUUUUGAGACAGAAUCUUGCUUUGUCUCCCAGGCUGGAGUGCAGUGGCAUGAUUGUAGCUUACUGCAGCUUCGACCUCCUGGGCUCAAACAAUCCACCUAUCUCAGCCUUCUGAGUAACUGGGACCAGAGAUGUGCACCAAAAUGCCUGGCUAAUUUGUUCAUUUUUUGUAAAGAUAGGGUCUCCCUAUGUUCCCCAGGCUAUUCUCCAUCUCCUGGGCUCCAGUGAUCCUCACGCCUCGGCCACCCAAAGUGCUGGGAUUAUAGAAGUGAACCACUGCGCCUGGCCUAUUGAAGGUUUUUAAUCUUCAGAGUUUCGACUUUAUCAACAACACUUAGAAGCCACCAAAGAAUUGCAGAUGGAUCCUAAUAGAAUAUCAGAAGAUGGCACUCACUGCAUUUAUAGAAUUUUGAGACUCCAUGAAAAUGCAGAUUUUCAAGACACAACUCUGGAGAGUCAAGAUACAAAAUUAAUACCUGAUUCAUGUAGGAGAAUUAAACAGGCCUUUCAAGGAGCUGUGCAAAAGGAAUUACAACAUAUCGUUGGAUCACAGCACAUCAGAGCAGAGAAAGCGAUGGUGGAUGGCUCAUGGUUAGAUCUGGCCAAGAGGAGCAAGCUUGAAGCUCAGCCUUUUGCUCAUCUCACUAUUAAUGCCACCGACAUCCCAUCUGGUUCCCAUAAAGUGAGUCUGUCCUCUUGGUACCAUGAUCGGGGUUGGGCCAAGAUCUCCAACAUGACUUUUAGCAAUGGAAAACUAAUAGUUAAUCAGGAUGGCUUUUAUUACCUGUAUGCCAACAUUUGCUUUCGACAUCAUGAAACUUCAGGAGACCUAGCUACAGAGUAUCUUCAACUAAUGGUGUACGUCACUAAAACCAGCAUCAAAAUCCCAAGUUCUCAUACCCUGAUGAAAGGAGGAAGCACCAAGUAUUGGUCAGGGAAUUCUGAAUUCCAUUUUUAUUCCAUAAACGUUGGUGGAUUUUUUAAGUUACGGUCUGGAGAGGAAAUCAGCAUCGAGGUCUCCAACCCCUCCUUACUGGAUCCGGAUCAGGAUGCAACAUACUUUGGGGCUUUUAAAGUUCGAGAUAUAGAUUGAGCCCCAGUUUUUGGAGUGUUAUGUAUUUCCUGGAUGUUUGGAAACAUUUUUUAAAACAAGCCAAGAAAGAUGUAUAUAGGUGUGUGAGACUACUAAGAGGCAUGGCCCCAACGGUACACGACUCAGUAUCCAUGCUCUUGACCUUGUAGAGAACACGCGUAUUUACAGCCAGUGGGAGAUGUUAGACUCAUGGUGUGUUACACAAUGGUUUUUAAAUUUUGUAAUGAAUUCCUAGAAUUAAACCAGAUUGGAGCAAUUACGGGGUGACCUUAUGAGAAACUGCAUGUGGGCUAUGGGAGGGGUUGGUCCCUGGUCAUGUGCCCCUUCGCAGCUGAAGUGGAGAGGGUGUCAUCUAGCGCAAUUGAAGGAUCAUCUGAAGGGGCAAAUUCUUUUGAAUUGUUACAUCAUGCUGGAACCUGCAAAAAAUACUUUUUCUAAUGAGGAGAGAAAAUAUAUGUAUUUUUAUAUAAUAUCUAAAGUUAUAUUUCAGAUGUAAUGUUUUCUUUGCAAAGUAUUGUAAAUUAUAUUUGUGCUAUAGUAUUUGAUUCAAAAUAUUUAAAAAUGUCUUGCUGUUGACAUAUUUAAUGUUUUAAAUGUACAGACAUAUUUAACUGGUGCACUUUGUAAAUUCCCUGGGGAAAACUUGCAGCUAAGGAGGGGAAAAAAAUGUUGUUUCCUAAUAUCAAAUGCAGUAUAUUUCUUCGUUCUUUUUAAGUUAAUAGAUUUUUUCAGACUUGUCAAGCCUGUGCAAAAAAAUUAAAAUGGAUGCCUUGAAUAAUAAGCAGGAUGUUGGCCACCAGGUGCCUUUCAAAUUUAGAAACUAAUUGACUUUAGAAAGCUGACAUUGCCAAAAAGGAUACAUAAUGGGCCACUGAAAUCUGUCAAGAGUAGUUAUAUAAUUGUUGAACAGGUGUUUUUCCACAAGUGCCGCAAAUUGUACCUUUUUUGUUUUUUCAAAAUAGAAAAGUUAUUAGUGGUUUAUCAGCAAAAAAGUCCAAUUUUAAUUUAGUAAAUGUUAUCUUAUACUGUACAAUAAAAACAUUGCCUUUGAAUGUUAAUUUUUUGGUACAAAAAUAAAUUUAUAUGAAAACCUGC